AGAGCUGUCGGAGAAGCGGGACCGCGAGGCCGGCGCGCGGCGCUCUGCGCGGUCAGAGGGAGCGCCUGGCAGCAGCAGGAGCAGCAGCAGCAGCCCGCGGCGGGGCCGCCGCCAGCCGCCGCGACCGCCGCGGCUGCAGCCUCCGAAGGGAGGCCGGGUGAGCCGGCGUACGCACUUUCCCGCGGACUUUCGGAGUGUUUGUGGAUAUACAUGCCAAGCCGCCACGAUGAUGUCCAUGAACAGCAAGCAGCCUCACUUUGCCAUGCAUCCCACCCUCCCUGAGCACAAGUACCCGUCGCUGCACUCCAGCUCCGAGGCCAUCCGGCGGGCCUGCCUGCCCACGCCGCCGCUGCAGAGCAACCUCUUCGCCAGCCUGGACGAGACGCUGCUGGCGCGGGCCGAGGCGCUGGCGGCCGUGGACAUCGCCGUGUCCCAGGGCAAGAGCCAUCCUUUCAAGCCGGACGCCACGUACCACACGAUGAACAGCGUGCCGUGCACGUCCACUUCCACGGUGCCUCUGGCGCACCACCACCACCACCACCACCACCACCAGGCGCUCGAACCCGGCGAUCUGCUGGACCACAUCUCCUCGCCGUCGCUCGCGCUCAUGGCCGGCGCGGGCGGCGCGGGCGCGGCGGCCGGCGGCGGCGGCGCCCACGACGGCCCGGGGGGCGGUGGCGGCCCGGGCGGCGGCGGCGGCCCGGGCGGCGGCCCCGGGGGAGGCGGCGGUGGCGGCCCGGGGGGCGGCGGCGGCGGCCCGGGCGGCGGGCUCCUGGGCGGCUCCGCGCACCCUCACCCGCAUAUGCACAGCCUGGGCCACCUGUCGCACCCCGCGGCGGCGGCCGCCAUGAACAUGCCGUCCGGGCUGCCGCACCCCGGGCUGGUGGCGGCGGCGGCGCACCACGGCGCGGCAGCGGCAGCGGCGGCGGCGGCGGCCGGGCAGGUGGCAGCGGCAUCGGCGGCGGCGGCCGUGGUGGGCGCAGCGGGCCUGGCGUCCAUCUGCGACUCGGACACGGACCCGCGCGAGCUCGAGGCGUUCGCGGAGCGCUUCAAGCAGCGGCGCAUCAAGCUGGGCGUGACGCAGGCCGACGUGGGCUCGGCGCUGGCCAACCUCAAGAUCCCGGGCGUGGGCUCACUCAGCCAGAGCACCAUCUGCAGGUUCGAGUCGCUCACGCUCUCGCACAACAACAUGAUCGCGCUCAAGCCCAUCCUGCAGGCGUGGCUCGAGGAGGCCGAGGGCGCCCAGCGCGAGAAAAUGAACAAGCCUGAGCUCUUCAACGGCGGCGAGAAGAAGCGCAAGCGGACUUCCAUCGCCGCGCCCGAGAAGCGCUCCCUCGAGGCCUACUUCGCCGUGCAGCCCCGGCCCUCGUCCGAGAAGAUCGCCGCCAUCGCCGAGAAACUGGACCUCAAAAAGAACGUGGUGCGGGUGUGGUUUUGCAACCAGAGACAGAAGCAGAAGCGGAUGAAAUUCUCUGCCACUUACUGAGGGGGCUGGGAGGUGUCGGGCGGGACAGAAUGGGGAGCUGAGGAGGCAUUUUUGGGGGGCUUUCCUCUGCUUGCCUCCCCUCGGAUUUGGAGUGUCCGUUAUCCUGCCUGCAUUUGGGGAGUCCCUUCUCGCUCUCUUUCCUCCACCCAUUCUCUGAUUUUCCUGCCUUUGCUGUCCCCUAGCCUUGAGGACUGGGGUGCUGGGUGUGGGGAUUGGAGUAUAGGGUAGGGGAGAAGGGGGGGAGCAUUCGGGGGAGUGGGGAGUGGGGGGAAGGAAAGCGGAGACCCGAGCAGGGGUUUUAAGGAGCAGGAUGGUUCUGGGGUUUGGGUGGGGGGAGACGCGGGAAGGGUAGGAAAAUGGACUGUUUCUGACCAGAGACACUUACCUAAAUAUCCUGGGGACCAAGGAACUAUGUACAAAAACAAACCUACCAACCACCAAAAACUAGACAAAUAAAGACAAACUAAAACAAAACAGAACAAAAGCAAAGGAAAAUGCUUUAGAAAUUUUAACUCCGGGGAGCCAUAAUCUGCAACUUCAUUUUCCCCCAUAGAAGAGAAAAAAGAGCACCACCAUUAUUACCACCUCCCCAACCCUACACGCACGAACUGAGUCGAAAAACGAAAACCAAACGAGCGAGAAGUUGAAGUUCUGGGUAUCAAAGCUAGUUGUUCUGUCUGCGUGUUUAAUUUUUCCCUCUCUCACCUCCACCCCAUCCAUAUCCUCUUUAUUUCCUCCGUUCCAAUGAGAGGCCUAUGGCUGCUCUCCAAUCCCGGGAAGUGAGUGGGAGCACAGCUGAAAAGAGAGGGUCAGGGGGAGGCUGGCUGCUUGCUUAGGUGGAAUCCAAGUUUUCCCGUGGCCCUGCCUAUACUCUGGUGGCCUGGUCCUGUUGGGGUGGGGGUCUUUGGAGAGAAGGGCAUAGUCUUUGAGCUACUAAAAAGCAGAAUUCCGGAGCUUCGAGAUAUCUUAUUCUAGGAAAAUGAAACAAUUUUAACAACAGUUUUUUUUCCUCUUAUGUCGAAGAUCUAGUUUUAGACAAUUUCAAAAUAAGCUUUUCCCACUCAUAGAACUUUAACUUGCCCUUUCAGUUUUAUCUUUUUUUUAGAGAGAGGUUUAAACUACUGAUUUUUCCUGUUGAUUCAAAUAGACUAAUGGGGUGAAAGUUAUUAGGAGAGAUACUCUCUCCUGUUUUCUCCACUGAACGAGACUCAUCUUGCUCUUCUAGGUCCCGUUUCUUCCUCUCUUGGAGGACAUGAAAUUAUAGAAAUGUUGAGAAGUUCCUGCUUUCUUUUGCGGUAGGACUUGGCUGUGAGAAAAUCACCUAAAUCCCAGAAAAGAGGAAGACAGAUUUAAAGUGCCCCCACCCCCAUUUGUUUCAAAGAGGUCUGCAUGUUGGGCGAAAACAGAACAACUGUGUUUCCUUUUACUUGUUCUUAUUAUUCAAGAGUCAUUUAUUACAGGGGAUAAAUGUUGGGUAGCAAGAACUUUAAUUUGCACUACCAGUCUCCCAAAUAGAAAAUCAUGUAUAGUAUUUCAUAGUAAUAAUCAGGUACCUUACAAGCUGCUGGUGGAUUUUAAAAAAUUAAGAUAGUUGAAGGUGGUUAGGUAAAAUGCCUGCUUUGUGUACAAGAUACUCUUUGGAUCUCUCGUAGAGAUGGUUUGUUACCAUCCUUUAAUCAUAACUAAAACAUUGAAAACAGAACAAAUGAGAAAAGAAAAAAAACCUGCCGAUUAACAAGACUGAAAUCAUGCAUGAUCUGAAAGGUGUGGAAAGAAACACAAUUAGGUCUCACUCUGGUUAGGCAUUAUUUAUUUAAUUAUGUUGUAUAUCAUUGUUUGCAGGGCAAACAUUCUAUGCAUUUGAAACUGAGCACUAAACUGGGCUAGCUUUCUGGUAGACCGUUUUGUGGCUAGUGCGAUUUCACAGUCUACUGCCUGUUUCCACUGAAAACAUUUUUGUCAUAUUCUUGUAUUCAAAGAAAAAGGAAAAAAGAUUAUUGUAAAUAUUUUAUUUAAUGCACACAUUCACACAGUGGUAACAGACUGCCAGUGUUCAUCCUGAAAUGUCUCACGGAUUGAUCUACCUGUCCAUGUAUGUCUGCUGAGCUUUCUCCUUGGUUAUGUUUUUUCUCUUUUACCUUUCUCCUCCCUUACUUCUAUCAGAACCAAUUCUAUGCGCCAAAAUACAACAGGGGGAUGUGUCCCAGUACACUUACAAAUAAAACAUAACUGAAAGAAGAGCAGUUUUAUGAUUUGGGUGCGUUUUUGUGUUUAUACUGGGCCAGGUCCUGGUAGAACCUUUCAACAAACAACCAAACAAAAAGAAAACACAAAGAAAUGGGGGGAGGGUAGGGUGUUGAAGGGGGACAAAAAGGGGAGAGAUUGAGAAUGAUGUAUUUUUUUGCUGAAUCAGAAUUCACUUUCAGAUAACUCAUGAAAAGUGGUGCUCUAAAUAAAAUGAAUUCUAUAUUAGUUGCCUGUGUUUAUAAAAGUUAUUAUUUUUUAACUGCAGAAACUCUUAAACCACAGCACUUGAUCCAGAGUGGUGAAAACCAAUAAAUAACCAGGCACCCAAAAAACAUUUAAAUUUAGGGUCAGGGACAGAGGAAUUUGGAGGUUUAGAUGUGAUAUUCUACCCUAAAAACACCUAGUAACUGAAUGGCUUUUCUUUGGAGGGUAAUACAUUUUAAAACAUUUAGUGUGCCACCUACUGCUCCACAGUGACUAGAGAGCCUCUAUUUCUUGGUGACUUGGGACUAGAUCAGAUGCCAAAUGUACAAAGUUUCUUAAGAGUUGAGAUUAUAUCAUCUGAAGUCAUCUUAUUUUAGCCAAAUCUUUUUAAUUUCACCGGCAAAUCUGUGAAGGAAAACACUUGAUGUUCAAAAAGAAUAGUACAUUUUAAAAGCUGCGAUUUUAAACAGUUGUUAAUGUUAAAAAAAAAAAGCACUAGAGGUAUUUUUAAACAUAGAACUCUUCCAUAAAAAGUUGAUUUGUUUUUGCUGUUAUUGACUUGAAACAUCAUCAGUUUUAAAUAAAAUGCAUUUGUAAAAAAA